UGGGGACCUGAGACUGAGUUCAAGACCCAGGAGGGGAGGCGAGGUUGUUGGGGCAGUAUUUUCAAGUGGAGGGAGUUUGAAGCUGGGACGUUGGGCUUUUGGAGAAGCGAGAGAACAGAGGGGAGGAACUUUUGAGACAGGGAACCUGGAGAUUCGAUUCCACUUGGGUCUUCCGGACGGGUUGAAUUCGGGGCUUUAUCGUGUUCUGGAAAAGGUGUGAGAGUCCCUAUUUUACAGAUGAGGAAACUGAGGCCCUGAGAAUUGACUCAUUCAGAUCACUUCCCAUGAUCACGCAGCUGAGCAGUUUCCAAUACAGAAUUCAGAUUUGGGGUUCCCUACUUCCAAUCCAGGGCAUCAUGGUGGGAGGCUUGAAGAGGAAACACUCUGAUUUGGAAGAGGAGGAGGAGAGGUGGGAGUGGAGUCCAGCAGGCCUUCAGAGCUACCAGCAAGCCCUGCUCCGCAUCUCCCUAGACAAAGUCCAGCGCAGCCUGGGCCCCCGAGCACCCAGCCUCCGCAGGCAUGUCCUCAUCCAUAACACCCUCCAACAGCUGCAGGCUGCACUUCGCCUGGCUCCCGCCCCUGCCCUGCCCCCCGAGCCCCUCUUCCUGGGCGAGGAGGAUUUCUCCCUGUCAGCCACCAUUGGCUCUAUCCUCAGGGAGCUGGACACCUCCAUGGAUGGGACUGAGCCCCCUCAGAAUCCAGUGACUCCCCUUGGCCUCCAGAAUGAAGUGCCACCCCAGCCUGAUCCAGUCUUCUUAGAAGCUCUGAGCUCCCGGUACUUGGGGGACUCUGGCCUGGAUGACUUCUUUCUGGACAUUGACACAUCUGCGGUAGAAAAGGAGCCUGCACGGGCCCCACCAGAGCCUCCUCACAACCUCUUCUGUGCCCCAGGUUCUUGGGAGUGGAAUGAACUGGAUCACAUCAUGGAAAUCAUUCUGGGGUCCUAAAACUGUGAUAGAGGGGAUCGAUCCUUCCUCAUGUCAUCUUCGGUGGCCUGGAUCCCUGAAUGCAACUCUGGGUGUGUGUUUUUGUGGGGGCUCGAAGCAGUGACUAUGGCCUCCUUUGUUCCCAUUUCAGGGUUCCACAAACUGUCUUGCAUGUGUGUGUGUGUCUGGUUACCCCGACCUUCUGUGAAGGUGGGUCUUCCUGAAUUAAUUUAUCUAUUCCAAAUGCCUUAACGAGACUCUGUUUCUGGGAGUCUGAUUUUCCACUUACACAUUUCUUCCACCUUUCCUGCUAGUUCCCACUCCCCUGUGACCACUGGGGCCUCAGGGAAGAUAAAGAAAGCUGGGCCUGUCGAAGGAUGACAGGGAUGUGCUGCCAGGUUGCUAUAGAAACCCAGGCUCUGCCUCUUGCACCUUGAGGGGGUGGGAGGGGCUGGUGUCCUCCCUCCAGGCUGAACCCCACUUCCUCGGCAGGACCCCAGUCUCAGCAGCCUCCUGAUUUCAUAACCAGGCCGGACCACGUGCAAUAGGGUGGAAACCAAACUGCUCCAUGCCGGGUUAUUUAAAAGAAAGGCAGAGUUUGUGGUGGCUUUUUUUUUUUUUUUUGGAUUGUUUGUAAUUUUUUUAAAUAAAAGUAUUUUGGAAGGAG